AGACCUUGUAGAGACGGCGGCGGCGCCCGCGGGCUGGGAGCCGGGGCCCGCAGGUGGAAGCGCACCCGGGAGGCGGGCCGGCCGGGGCUGGAGCGGCUCGGGCGGGCUCUUGACGCUCAGCCAGCUUCGCUCCGGCCUCGGGAAGGCGCGCGUCCCGCCCUGACCCGCCGGCCUCUCCCACCCCAGCAGUGACGCGCCGCCUGGGAGCUGGAGCCCGCGCAGCGCCCCGCAGGGCGAUGGACGGCCGAACCCCGCGCCCGCAGGACGCCCCAGCCAGGAGAAAACCAAAAGCCAAGGCACCACUUCCUCCAGCUGAGACCAAAUAUACUGAUGUCUCUUCAGCUGCUGAUUCUGUAGAAUCCACUGCUUUCAUCAUGGAACAGAAAGAAAACAUGAUAGAUAAAGACGUUGAACUCUCAGUGGUCCUACCUGGGGAUAUUAUCAAAUCUACUACUGUUCAUGGCAGUAAACCUAUGAUGGACUUGUUGAUAUUCCUUUGUGCACAGUAUCACUUAAAUCCAUCAAGUUACACAAUCGAUCUGUUGUCAGCUGAACAGAACCACAUUAAAUUUAAGCCAAACACACCAAUAGGAAUGUUGGAGGUAGAGAAGGUAAUUUUAAAGCCAAAAAUGUUGGAUAAGAAAAAACCUACACCUAUAAUACCAGAGAAAACUGUGAGAGUAGUGAUUAAUUUUAAGAAAACACAGAAGACCAUAGUGAGAGUGAGUCCACAUGCAUCGCUUCAAGAGCUUGCCCCUAUUAUAUGUAGCAAAUGUGAGUUUGAUCCGUUGCAUACACUAUUGUUGAAAGAUUAUCAAUCGCAGGAGCCUCUUGACUUGACAAAAUCUCUUAAUGACCUGGGACUAAGAGAAUUAUAUGCGAUGGAUGUCAACAGAGAGUCCUGCCAAAUAUCACAAAACCUAGAUAUUAUGAAGGAGAAAGAAAAUAAAGGGUUUUUCAGUUUUUUUCAACGCAGUAAGAAAAAGCGAGACCAAACUGCAAGUGCCCCUGCAACCCCUCUAGUAAAUAAGCACCGCCCAACUUUUACAAGGUCCAAUACCAUUUCCAAACCAUAUAUUUCCAACACCCUGCCGUCGGAUGCACCCAAGAAGAGGCGGGCUCCACUGCCCCCGAUGCCAGCAUCUCAGAGUGUCCCCCAAGACCUUGCACACAUCCAGGAGAGGCCUGCUUCUUGUAUAGUGAAAUCCAUGAGCGUGGAUGAGACAGAUAAGAGUCCCUGUGAAGCAGGAAGAGUGAGGGCAGGUUCACUGCAGCUCAGCAGCAUGUCUGCAGGGAAUUCAUCUUUGAGAAGGACAAAGCGAAAAGCACCUUCCCCACCCUCCAAAAUACCCCCGCAUCAAAGUGAUGAAAAUAGUCGUGUGACUGCCUUACAGCCAGUAGAUGGAGUUCCUCCAGACAGUGCUUCAGAAGCAAACUCUCCUGAGGAGCUAUCCAGCCCAGAAACCUUUCACCCUGGGCUUUCCAGUCAGGAGCAGUGCACUGCGCCCAAACUGAUGGAGGAAACCUCUGUCUUUGAGUGCCCUGGGACACCUGAGGCAGCCAUAACAUCAUUGACAUCUGGAAUAAGCUCUGAUUAUAGCCUUGAAGAGAUAGAUGAAAAGGAAGAACUGAGUGAAGUGCCUAAAGUUGAAGCUGAAAAUAUUUCUCCGAAGUCACAAGAUAUUCCUUUUGUAUCUACUGAUAUAAUAAAUACACUGAAAAAUGAUCCUGACUCAGCCCUUGGCAAUGGUAGUGGAGAGUUCUCACAAAACUCCAUGGAAGAAAAACAAGAAACUAAAAGCACAGAUGGACAAGAACCACACAGUGUAGUAUAUGAUACAAGCAAUGGAAAGAAGGUAGUUGACAGUAUAAGAAACUUGAAGUCGUUGGGCCCAAACCAAGAGAAUGUUCAAAAUGAAAUAAUUGUCUAUCCAGAGAACACAGAAGACAAUAUGAAAAAUGGAGUGAAGAAAACAGAAAUCAAUGUAGAAGGUGUUGCCAAAAAUAACAACAUUGAUAUGGAAGUUGAGAGACCAUCAAACUCUGAGGCACAUGAAACUGAUACUGCUAUAAGUUACAAGGAAAACCAUCUAGCAGCUUCAUCAGUACCAGAUCAAAAACUGAAUCAACCCAGUGCAGAAAAGACAAAAGAUGCAGCAAUUCAGACAACCCCUUCUUGUAACAGUUUUGAUGGGAAACACCAAGAUCAUAAUUUAUCUGACUCCAAAGUUGAAGAAUGUGUGCAAACUUCAAAUAACAACAUAUCAACUCAACACUCAUGCUUAAGUUCACAAGAUUCUGUAAAUACCUCAAGGGAAUUCAGGAGUCAAGGCACCCUAAUUAUACAUUCAGAAGAUCCGCUUACCGUAAAAGAUCCAAUUUGUGCACAUGGUAAUGAUGAUCUUUUGCCUCCUGUAGAUAGGAUUGACAAAAAUUCCACUGCUUCUUACCUAAAGAAUUACCCACUUUAUAGACAGGACUACAAUCCCAAGCCAAAACCUUCAAAUGAAAUUACACGAGAGUAUAUACCCAAAAUUGGCAUGACUACUUAUAAAAUAGUGCCUCCCAAAUCCUUGGAAAUAUCGAAAGACUGGCAAUCAGAAACCAUAGAGUAUAAAGAUGAUCAGGACAUGCAUGCUUUAGGGAAAAAGCACACUCAUGAGAAUGUGAAAGAAACUGCCAUCCAAACAGAAGAUUCUGCUAUUUCUGAAAGCCCAGAAGAGCCACUGCCAAACCUUAAACCGAAGCCUAACCUGAGAACAGAGCAUCAAGUGCCCAGUUCUGUGAGCUCACCUGAUGAUGCCAUGGUUAGUCCUCUGAAACCUGCUCCCAAAAUGACAAGAGACACUGGCACAGCUCCUUUUGCACCAAAUUUGGAAGAAAUAAACAAUAUUUUGGAAUCAAAAUUUAAAUCUCGGGCUUCAAAUGCCCAGGCCAAACCCAGCUCUUUUUUUUUGCAGAUGCAGAAGAGAGUAUCGGGUCACUAUGUGACAUCUGCAGCUGCCAAGAGUGUCCAUGCUGCCCCUAAUCCUGCUCCAAAAGAACUGACAAAUAAAGAGGCAGAAAGGGAUAUGCUGCCUUCUCCGGAGCAGACUCUUUCUCCCUUAAGUAAAAUGCCUCACUCUGUUCCACAACCCCUUGUUGAAAAAACUGAUGAUGAUGUCAUCGGUCAGGCUCCUGCUGAAGCCUCCCCUCCUCCCAUAGCUCCAAAACCUGUGACAAUUCCUGCUAGUCAGGUAUCCACACAAAAUCUGAAGACUUUGAAAACUUUUGGUGCCCCACGACCAUACUCAAGUUCUGGUCCUUCACCGUUUGCUCUUGCUGUAGUGAAAAGGUCACAGUCUUUCAGUAAAGAGCGCACCGAGUCACCUAGUGCCAGUGCAUUGGUCCAACCUCCAGCCAACACAGAGGAAGGGAAGACUCAUUCUGUAAAUAAAUUUGUGGACAUCCCACAGCUUGGUGUGUCUGAUAAGGAAAAUAACUCUGCACAUAAUGAACAGAAUUCCCAAAUACCAACUCCAACUGAUGGCCCAUCAUUCACUGUUAUGAGACAAAGUUCUUUAACAUUCCAAAGCUCUGACCCAGAACAGAUGCGACAGAGUUUGCUGACUGCAAUCCGUUCGGGAGAGGCUGCUGCCAAAUUGAAAAGGGUUACCAUUCCAUCAAAUACAAUAUCUGUGAAUGGAAGGUCAAGACUCAGCCAUUCCAUGUCCCCUGAUGCCCAGGACGGCCAUUAAAUGUUACCCUGCCACACCACUGCACUUCACUUCCACUUCAGACCAACUUCAUACUAAUGGAACAUUUUGGCAAAUGUAUAUUCAGAUGUACACUAAUAUAUUAUCUAUUAAAAUAUUAGAAUUUGUGUUGUGGCUUUUAAUGCCAGAAGAAAAGUUACCAGAAUUUAUAAUUUAUAGUAAUUUUUUGAUCUUUUUUUUGCCUUAAGAGUUGAAUAUGCUGCUUUAGAACUUUAAAACAAGGUGUAAAUGAUUUUCAUUUUUUACAAAUGAAAAAUAAUUCCUUUGUAUUGAUUUCACUUACCAGCACAUUCUCUACAAUGGUGACUUAGACAAAAGUAUAAGAUUCAUAGACUUUAUAUUUGUAUGACAUACAACUAGGACAAACAUAGAUAUGACAUUUGCUGCCUCAGUGUAGCAAUUGGAAAUAUUUAUAAGUUAUAUGAAAGCCUGUUUUGGGCUGAAAGAAUGAUUUAGAAAACUAGUGAUACCAAAUAAGUAUAUUCAGUUCAAUAAUUAUUUUCAAUGAUGAAUCACUUAGUGUGAAAGACUUGCCUUGUGUAUUCUUUAUGUAAUUACAAAUCACUGUCAAUUUUAUGGGAAGCUCAUAGUAUUUUAAUAUUUUAUUAACAUGGAACUCUUGUUUUUUUAAUCUUUAGAACUUAAAUUCUACAAGAAUUUUAAAUAUUUUCUGUAUAUAAUUAUGACAUUGUCACACAGAAAUUACACAUUUUAUGUGCCAGAAGCCUUAAACAUCUUUCUGUGAAAAUGCUGAUAUAUUGUGACAGUUAUUUCACAUUUGAUAUGUAGAGAGGAAUAGGGGUUAGUUUAUGUUUAUAUUGAAAAACUUUAAAGACUAUUUGGAAGUUCCAGAAAUUCUGGUUUUAAUUCAAGUAAAAUGAUAAAAUAGUCAUUAUAUAGUUCAGAUGCUAAUAUUCUAAGUAAUAAUAUAUAUUUACAUUGAAGCUAAAACUGUUAAGCAAAACAAUGCCCAUUUGUCGGCUUACAGCUCUUCCGGAGUCUAGAGCCUGUUGGUGUUCUGUCCCUACUUUAAGAAUUUAAUUGCUCACUUAUUCUGAAAGCUUUGUUCAAACAAGAUGAUAUUAAAUUUGUUUUCACUAAAACUACUGGGAUAUCUGCCUCUUGGGGAUUUUUUUUUCAAUUUAAUAAAAGCAAGUUGUAUAUUUGGGGUGCUUUUUAAAAUAUAUAGUUUGUGUCAACCAGCAUAUUUAUUUCCCUUACCUGAUGCAUACAUUUCUAUUAGCCAGUGAACAAACAAGAAAUUUGUAAGAUUUACCAUUUAUCAGGGAUCCCUAGUGUACAUUUAAGCCCUGGCAUUCUGACUCCAAAAUGCAUGGUCUAAGCAUUUAAAAUGUUUAGCAUAGUUCCUGAUACAUGGCAUGGCCAUCUUAAAUGCUAAAUGUUGCUGCUGUUUUCCUUGAAUCAGUUGGAGAGACCCUCAUAUAUAGAUACUUAAGUUAUGUUGUUAUAAGCAAGUAGAGAAAGGAGUGAAUUUUUUUUAAAAAAUUGUGUUGUCAUAAUUAUCUACUUAUAAAAAUAUAAAUUUGGAUCCCUAAUUUAAACCUUCAUAUAUUUUGAGUUGGAUUGAAGACUUAAAGACAAGCGACAUGUAAGAUGUUUUCAAUAUAUUAAUAUAUAAGAAAGGCUUAAUUUAUGAAGAUAUGAAAGUUCCUACAACUCAUGAUAAGUCUACCUAAUAGAAAUAUCAGCACAUUAUUCUUACAAGAGGAAAUUCAAAAGGCCAACAAACAUGGAAAAAAAAUACUCUUCACUGAUAAUCAGGGAAAUACAAGUUAAAAACAUGGAAAGGUACCACAUCAAAUUAGCAAAAACGGAAGUUUCAAAAUAGCAAGUGUUGUCAGGAACAUCAAACAGUGGGAACUCUACUGUUGGUGGGAAAAUACACUGGCAUAACUACCAGUUCUGCAAUAUCUAGUAAAAUUAAAGAUUCCUUACCAUGUUACCUUAAAUAAGUACUUAUGCACAUGCAUAAGGAGACAUCUGCAAAAAUGUUCACGGCAGCCUUGUGUAAAACAGCAGAAAGGGGUCCUAACCCGUGCUCAGCUUUAGUAAUGCAUAUAUUCAUAUGAUAGACUUCCACACAGCAGUCCAAAUGAACAAGCUAGAGCUAUAUAUGUCAGCAUGAAUACAUCUCAAAAACAAGUGACAAGAGUGAGUGGUGGAACAAGUCGUGUUUUAUGAAAUUAGUUACAUAAAGUAUAAAUAUAAAAAAUGAUACUAUAAAUUAUGGCUGUAUAUGUAGGAAAAAAAUUUGCUGGUGGUUACCUGUGGGAACCAAGAAAGACUGAAUUGAGAUUUAUAAGAGGCAUCAAUUGUGUUCGUAGUAUUUUAUAAACUGCUGUUUGAAAACAAGUGCUUAUUAUAUUCUAAAUUCUAGUAUACUUGUAGUUUAUAAUUAUAAUAAAAUAAUGUUUUAAAGGUCACAUAGGAUUUAGGGGGCUAUGUAUAUAAACCAUUAAUACAUGUAUGUUCUGAAAAGUUGCCUUAUCGACACCAUUUUAGGAGAACAUGUGCUAUCCUGUCAAUGGGGAAAGAAAUUUGUGACAAGUAGUUUUCACUCAUCAUAUCCUAAAAUAACAGCACAAGGAAGAUACAGGAAUGGUCUAGAACCAACUUUUGACUUUCAUGUAUAAUUUUUAGCAUCUAGGCAUUUUGCUUUUCCUUCUUUCCUCCAAUCAAGUUAUUUAUUUAUAUAAUAUUAAAAUUAUAAUUCAGAUUACAUAUAUAUGAUAGAGUAUAAAAUACAUUCUUUUUCAUCCCCAGCAUCCCACUCUCCUCUCCAAAGAUAGCUGUUAAUAUUUUGAUAUGAAGCCCUAUAUAGAUGUAUUUAUAUGAAGUACAUGUGUGCAGGUUUGUUGGGGGCUUUUGUGUGUGUGUGUGUGUGUGUGUGUGUGUGUGUGUAUGUGUGUUUCUUAACAUGAAAGGAGGUCACACUCUAAUACUAUGUAACAACUUGCCUUUUAUACCAGCAGUGUUCUGGAAGAGCUUUUCUUUUUACACAUACAGAUCGAUCGUAUUUCUGUUAGCCAUUCUAUUGUUUCUUGCUGCGGUACAUAAUGUUGGCUGGAGUGAAGAGAUUGGGGUUCAGAUCACAAGUCUGCCACUUAUGAGUCAUGGGAUCUUGGGCAAAUUACUUUCUCUAUGCUUCAUUUUCUCUUCUGAAAAAUGAAUUAAUAUGAAUAAAAAUGAACCUUAUUUUAAAAACGGCAGGCAAUUCAUCUUUUAAAGUUACCUGAUGUCAAUACUAUAAGUGAACAGGUAUUAUUUGCCUAAUAUACUCCCUAUUCUUUGAGGAGUGACCCUUCUUCCGAUUUCACCUCUUCAUGAACUGCCAGAUCUGGCCUUGGCCACUAGGCACUGGCAACAGCAUACACACUCUGUCAUCUUAUCCAAGUCCUUGAAAUGAGACCAAUCUUUGUCCUGAGACUUAGUUACUUAUAGGUGCUUAAAACCCAAAGCGUCCCAAUUGAUACAAUUAUGUAUGUGUCUAAUUCCAGUUUACUUUGUACCCACUACCAGUAGAGAAAAUAAGUAUCAAAGAACUAAGAAUCAAACUCAUCAUUUUUAAAAUCUACUGAUUUUGAUAACUGACUUGAAAGAAAAGAACUUGCAAUUAGAGGUCAUAGUGAAGAUUUCCAGGGUCAAAGUGAUUUCUGAGGUUUUAGAUGUAAAAAUAUCUCCUAUUUAUUUGCUAUUUCAGAGUUGACAACAAGAUUUUUAUUUGAUCCACAUAUUUAAAAGGUGUGCAAAGAUUGCUACUUUACAAAGGUCACAGAAGCAGAGGAGUCUCAGAGUCCCACAUCCAAUUACUAAUUUGUUCUUCCCCAUGACUAAAUGUAGCAAAUGAUGAAGAAACUGGUGCUAGAUUUCAAGGGAUACCAGAAUAGGAAGUUAUUUGUUCUGAAUCUUCAGUUGGUUUUCCUUUUCUCUUAAAUGUUACCACUUUCCUGCAAAUUUCCAUCCUUAAUAUGUUAGACUGUUCAUAUAGAUACAUUGUGUUUACAACAAGGAAAAAAUGCCACCAUGUGCUCAGAACUUUUUUGACAGGUAUUUUGAGAAGAGUUGUGGAACAUUCUGGUAAUUUGUAGAGAUCUGUUGGCAUCUCUGCUUCACAAACUGGAAAAAAUCAUUUGUAAGUCUUGCUAAUUACUUUUCUUGGAGAAGAAAAAAAAUGCUACAGUUGCAAACAAAUGUAUAGUUUUCAAAAAGAAGCAACUUUUUUGCUCCCCAGUUUAUUCUUAGUUUCCAGCCCACGCCUUGCGAUAGCGAUAGGCAUAGUGAUGGCCUCAAUUCUUUCUCUCUUGCAUCCAUACCUUUUGCUGUGAUAGCAGUGAUGGCCUCAGUUCUUUCCCUCUCUUGCAUCCGUACCUUUUGCUGUGUGACUUUGCAGCUCCUCUCAUUAAAGAGGCAGAGCCCCCUCUCCCACCCAUAGGAGCAGGUUUUGAGAGUAACAGAAUGAAGUGAAAAUGACACUGUGCCAGUUCUAAGACCAGCCCUCAAAGGUUCAUGUGUUUCUGCUUGCUUUCACUGUAUUUGAAAUGUUGCUGUGAGAAAGACAUCUCUGAAACAGCUGAAUGGUCCUAAGAAAAGGAUGAGAGAUGCAGGGAGCAGAGCUCCCAACUGAGGCCAGCCUAGAUCACCUAAGAGCCAGGCCCCCAGUUUACUCUGAUGUGUAAGCAAUAAAUGCUUACCCCAGCAAUACCACCAAGGUUUGUGGUUGGUUUAUAUACAGCAUUAAUGUGGCAAUAGGUGCAAUACACCCUGUUAAACAAACCAUACACAUAUGACUCUAACCCUAAUCAUAAAUUGAUUCAGUCUGUUCAGUUCCACAACGCUGUUUCCUCCAGAAUCUCACAGAUGACUUACUAAAUCCAACACAAAUACACCUCAGACUUUCUGUCUAGCUCCCAACCAGUUAAAAGCAAUUCUAAAUAUUUUUUUUCUUAGUCGUAGUGCAAAAGUAUAUUCUCUCCCUUUCUCUAUAGUUUUCUCUCAUUUUGUCUUCAGACCUAGAAGCAUGAGAGCCCAGCUGUCAAAGUCAUCUAGACCCCCUUCAGAAGGUCAUUAAAUUUGUCUAUUUCACAGGAUUGCAAGAUAAAAUACAGAAUGCCCAGUUAAAUUUGAACUUCGGAUAAACAACAAAUUUUUUUUUAGUAUAAGCAUAUCCCAUACAAUAUUUGGGAUAUACUUAUAUUUUUAUAUUGUUUAUCUGACGUUCAAGCUAACUAGGCAUCCUGUAUUUUUCUUAGCUAAAUCUGGCAACUGUGCUAUUUCAUUGAAAACCUGAAAGUGUACAAAGAAGGAAGAAGCAGAAUCUGCCAUAUGAGUAAUAGAAGUGAGCAGGCCCAGGACUCCCUAAGUCAAGAAACCAAGAGGCGUCAUUACGGAAAAGAGUAACUCACCCUGUGUGCUCCUUGGUAGUUCUCCCUCAGCGAUGCCCCCAUGUUAUGAAUGGGGAAAAGUUCACUGAAGGGUUCAUAGUGAAGAAACUUUUUGGAUGAUUUCUGUUGGUGGGUUUUGGAUACCUUCAAGGGAUCAGAAAAUAAUAUACUUAGGAAAUUUUGGUAAUGUCAUCAUUACUCUCUACAUUAUUAUUAUGACGGUUACAAUUGUUAAAUCUAGGUGGUGGGUAUGUGGGUUAUAUUGUACAUGAUUUUUAACUUGUCUGCAUGUUUGAAAUUAUAAUAAAGUCAAUAAAUAAAUUAUUGAGACACUCCUG